GGAGCUCGCUGCCGCCGAGCUGAGAAGAUGCUGCUGUCCCUGGUGCUCCACACGUACUCCAUGCGCUACCUGCUGCCCAGCGUCGUGCUCCUGGGCACGGCGCCCACCUACGUGUUGGCCUGGGGGGUCUGGCGGCUGCUCUCCGCCUUCCUGCCCGCCCGCUUCUACCAAGCGCUGGACGACCGGCUCUACUGCGUCUACCAGAGCAUGGUGCUCUUCUUCUUCGAGAAUUACACCGGGGUCCAGAGAUUGGAUUCGUAGAUUAAACUUGAGAAACAAACCAUAAAAGUGGAAGGCCCUCUUUAACAAUAUUGCUAUAUGGAGAUUUGCCAAAAAAUAAAGAAAAUAUAAUAUAUUUAGCAAAUCAUCAAAGCACAGUUGACUGGAUUGUUGCUGACAUCUUGGCCAUCAGGCAGAAUGCGCUAGGACAUGUGCGCUACGUGCUGAAAGAAGGGUUAAAAUGGCUGCCAUUGUAUGGGUGUUACUUUGCUCAGCAUGGAGGAAUCUAUGUAAAGCGCAGUGCCAAAUUUAACGAGAAAGAGAUGCGAAACAAGUUGCAGAGCUACGUGGACGCAGGAACUCCAAUGUAUCUUGUGAUUUUUCCAGAAGGUACAAGGUAUAAUCCAGAGCAAACAAAAGUCCUUUCAGCUAGUCAGGCAUUUGCUGCCCAACGUGGCCUUGCAGUAUUAAAACAUGUGCUAACACCACGAAUAAAGGCAACUCACGUUGCUUUUGAUUGCAUGAAGAAUUAUUUAGAUGCAAUUUAUGAUGUUACGGUGGUUUAUGAAGGGAAAGACGAUGGAGGGCAGCGAAGAGAGUCACCGACCAUGACGGAAUUUCUCUGCAAAGAAUGUCCAAAAAUUCAUAUUCACAUUGAUCGUAUCGACAAAAAAGAUGUCCCAGAAGAACAAGAACAUAUGAGAAGAUGGCUGCAUGAACGUUUCGAAAUCAAAGAUAAGAUGCUUAUAGAAUUUUAUGAGUCACCAGAUCCAGAAAGAAGAAAAAGAUUUCCUGGGAAAAGUGUUAAUUCCAAAUUAAGUAUCAAGAAGACUUUACCAUCAAUGUUGAUCUUAAGUGGUUUGACUGCAGGCAUGCUUAUGACCGAUGCUGGAAGGAAGCUGUAUGUGAACACCUGGAUAUAUGGAACCCUACUUGGCUGCCUGUGGGUUACUAUUAAAGCAUAGACAAGUAGCUGUCUCCAGACAGUGGGAUGUGCUACAUUGUCUAUUUUUGGCGGCUGCACAUGACAUCAAAUUGUUUCCUGAAUUUAUUAAGGAGUGUAAAUAAAGCCUUGUUGAUUGAAGAUUGGAUAAUAGAAUUUGUGACGAAAGCUGAUAUGCAAUGGUCUUGGGCAAACAUACCUGGUUGUACAACUUUAGCAUCGGGGCUGCUGGAAGGGUAAAAGCUAAAUGGAGUUUCUCCUGCUCUGUCCAUUUCCUAUGAACUAAUGACAACUUGAGAAGGCUGGGAGGAUUGUGUAUUUUGCAAGUCAGAUGGCUGCAUUUUUGAGCAUUAAUUUGCAGCGUAUUUCACUUUUUCUGUUAUUUUCAAUUUAUUACAACUUGACAGCUCCAAGCUCUUAUUACUAAAGUAUUUAGUAUCUUGCAGCUAGUUAAUAUUUCAUCUUUUGCUUAUUUCUACAAGUCAGUGAAAUAAAUUGUAUUUAGGAAGUGUCAGGAUGUUCAAAGGAAAGGGUAAAAAGUGUUCAUGGGGAAAAAGCUCUGUUUAGCACAUGAUUUUAUUGUAUUGCGUUAUUAGCUGAUUUUACUCAUUUUAUAUUUGCAAAAUAAAUUUCUAAUAUUUAUUGAAAUUGCUUAAUUUGCACACCCUGUACACACAGAAAAUGGUAUAAAAUAUGAGAACGAAGUUUAAAAUUGUGACUCUGAUUCAUUAUAGCAGAACUUUAAAUUUCCCAGCUUUUUGAAGAUUUAAGCUACACUAUUAGUACUUCCCUUUGUCUGUGCCAUAAGUGCUUGAAAACGUUAAGGUUUUCUGUUUUGUUUUGUUUUUUUAAUAUCAAAAGAGUCGGUGUGAACCUUGGUUGGACCCCAAGUUCACAAGAUUUUUAAGGUGAUGAGAGCCUGCAGACAUUCUGCCUAGAUUUACUAGCGUGUGCCUUUUGCCUGCUUCUCUUUGAUUUCACAGAAUAUUCAUUCAGAAGUCGCGUUUCUGUAGUGUGGUGGAUUCCCACUGGGCUCUGGUCCUUCCCUUGGAUCCCGUCAGUGGUGCUGCUCAGCGGCUUGCACGCAGACUUGCUAGGAAGAAAUGCAGAGCCAGCCUGUGCUGCCCACUUUCAGAGUUGAACUCUUUAAGCCCUUGUGAGUGGGCUUCACCAGCUACUGCAGAGGCAUUUUGCAUUUGUCUGUGUCAAGAAGUUCACCUUCUCAAGCCAGUGAAAUACAGACUUAAUUUGUCAUGACUGAACGAAUUUGUUUAUUUCCCAUUAGGUUUAGUGGAGCUACACAUUAAUAUGUAUCGCCUUAGAGCAAGAGCUGUGUUCCAGGAACCAGAUCACGAUUUUUAGCCAUGGAACAAUAUAUCCCAUGGGAGAAGACCUUUCAGUGUGAACUGUUCUAUUUUUGUGUUAUAAUUUAAACUUCGAUUUCCUCAUAGUCCUUUAAGUUGACAUUUCUGCUUACUGCUACUGGAUUUUUGCUGCAGAAAUAUAUCAGUGGCCCACAUUAAACAUACCAGUUGGAUCAUGAUAAGCAAAAUGAAAGAAAUAAUGAUUAAGGGAAAAUUAAGUGACUGUGUUACACUGCUUCUCCCAUGCCAGAGAAUAAACUCUUUCAAGCAUCAUCUUUGAAGAGUCGUGUGGUGUGAAUUGGUUUGUGUACAUUAGAAUGUAUGCACACAUCCAUGGACACUCAGGAUAUAGUUGGCCUAAUAAUCGGGGCAUGGGUAAAACUUAUGAAAAUUUCCUCAUGCUGAAUUGUAAUUUUCUCUUACCUGUAAAGUAAAAUUUAGAUCAAUUCCAUGUCUUUGUUAAGUACAGGGAUUUAAUAUAUUUUGAAUAUAAUGGGUAUGUUCUAAAUUUGAACUUUGAGAGGCAAUACUGUUGGAAUUAUGUGGAUUCUAACUCAUUUUAACAAGGUAGCCUGACCUGCAUAAGAUCACUUGAAUGUUAGGUUUCAUAGAACUAUACUAAUCUUCUCACAAAAGGUCUAUAAAAUACAGUCGUUGAAAAAAAUUUUGUAUCAAAAUGUUUGGAAAAUUAGAAGCUUCUCCUUAACCUGUAUUGAUACUGACUUGAAUUAUUUUCUAAAAUUAAGAGCCGUAUACCUACCUGUAAGUCUUUUCACAUAUCAUUUAAACUUUUGUUUGUAUUAUUACUGAUUUACAGCUUAGUUAUUAAUUUUUCUUUAUAAGAAUGCCGUCGAUGUGCAUGCUUUUAUGUUUUUCAGAAAAGGGUGUGUUUGGAUGAAAGUAAAAAAAAAAAUAAAAUCUUUCACUGUCUCUAAUGGCUGUGCUGUUUAACAUUUUUUGACCCUAAAAUUCACCAACAGUCUCCCAGUACAUAAAAUAGGCUUAAUGACUGGCCCUGCAUUCUUCACAAUAUUUUUCCCUAAGCUUUGAGCAAAGUUUUAAAAAAAUACACUAAAAUAAUCAAAACUGUUAAGCAGUAUAUUAGUUUGGUUAUAUAAAUUCAUCUGCAAUUUAUAAGAUGCAUGGCCGAUGUUAAUUUGCUUGGCAAUUCUGUAAUCAUUAAGUGAUCUCAGUGAAACAUGUCAAAUGCCUUAAAUUAACUAAGUUGGUGAAUAAAAGUGCCGAUCUGGCUAACUCUUACACCAUACAUACUGAUAGUUUUUCAUAUGUUUCAUUUCCAUGUGAUUUUUAAAAUUUAGAGUGGCAACAAUUUUGCUUAAUAUGGGUUACAUAAGCUUUAUUUUUUCCUUUGUUCAUAAUUAUAUUCUUUGAAUAGGUCUGUGUCAAUCAAGUGAUCUAACUAGACUGAUCAUAGAUAGAAGGAAAUAAGGCCAAGUUCAAGACCAGCCUGGGCAACAUAUCGAGAACCUGUCUACAAAAAAAUUAAAAAAAAUUAGCCAGGCAUGGUGGCGUACACUGAGUAGUUUGUCCCAGCUACUCGGGAGGGUGAGGUGGGAGGAUCGCUUCAGCCCAGGAGGUUGAGAUUGCAGUGAGCCAUGGACAUACCACUGCACUACAGCCUAGGUAACAGCACGAGACCCCAACUCUUAGAAAAUGAAAAGGAAAUAUAGAAAUAUAAAAUUUGCUUAUUAUAGACACACAGUAACUCCCAGAUAUGUACCACAAAAAAUGUGAAAAGAGAGAGAAAUGUCUACCAAAGCAGUAUUUUGUGUGUAUAAUUGCAAGCGCAUAGUAAAAUAAUUUUAACCUUAAUUUGUUUUUAGUAGUGUUUAGAUUGAAGAUUGAGUGAAAUAUUUUCUUGGCAGAUAUUCCGUAUCUGGUGGAAAGCUACAAUGCAAUGUCGUUGUAGUUUUGCAUGGCUUGCUUUAUAAACAAGAUUUUUUCUCCCUCCUUUUGGGCCAGUUUUCAUUACGAGUAACUCACACUUUUUGAUUAAAGAACUUGAAAUUACGUUAUCACUUAGUAUAAUUGACAUUAUAUAGAGACUAUGUAACAUGCAAUCAUUAGAAUCAAAAUUAGUACUUUGGUCAAAAUAUUUACAACAUUCACAUACUUGUCAAAUAUUCAUGUAAUUAACUGAAUUUAAAACCUUCAACUAUUAUGAAGUGCUCGUCUGUACAAUCGCUAAUUUACUCAGUUUAGAGUAGCUACAACUCUUCGAUACUAUCAUCAAUAUUUGACAUCUUUUCCAAUUUGUGUAUGAAAAGUAAAUCUAUUCCUGUAGCAACUGGGGAGUCAUAUAUGAGGUCAAAGACAUAUACCUUGUUAUUAUAAUAUGUAUACUAUAAUAAUAGCUGGUUAUCCUGAGCAGGGGAAAAGGUUAUUUUUAGGAAAACCACUUCAAAUAGAAAGCUGAAGUACUUCUAAUAUACUGAGGGAAGUAUAAUAUGUGGAACAAACUCUCAACAAAAUGUUUAUUGAUGUUGAUGAAACAGAUCAGUUUUUCCAUCCGGAUUAUUAUUGGUUCAUGAUUUUAUAUGUGAAUAUGUAAGAUAUGUUCUGCAAUUUUAUAAAUGUUCAUGUCUUUUUUUAAAAAAGGUGCUAUUGAAAUUCUGUGUCUCCAGCAGGCAAGAAUACUUGACUAACUCUUUUUGUCUCUUUAUGGUAUUUUCAGAAUAAAGUCUGACUUGUGUUUUUGAGAUUAUUGGUGCCUCAUUAAUUCAGCAAUAAAGGAAAAUAUGCAUCUCAAAAA